GCCCGCCAGCCCAGGAAGCACAAAGACGGAGGCGUCAUCCUGUCGUCGUGGCCCGAGACCUGGCUCCCGGCGUCCCUGGCUCGCUCCACAGCACGGUCGGGAAACAAUGCACGGCGUGCCGCCUCUGCGGGGCCGGCCUCUAGGCCGCUCGCCUCCGCGGCGGCGCCCGGCGUGGGCACCACGACCCAGAGAAACAAAGAGGCCGAGGCGGCGGCCGCGCCCCCUGCCCGUUGCAGCCCCCCCUAGCUCUCCCCUAAGAGGAGCCGUUCGGGGUCGGGGGUCGGGGGUCGGGGAUCCGCGUGGGGCCUGCAGGCGAAGGGCUGGCCGGGCCUGCUGAGCUGCUGUUCUGCAUGACUCAGUGGUUUUCGGAGAGGGCCCUGUUGGGCUUUAUUGAGUGAGGCCUUUGCUUAGAGGGGGAUGGGGUAUCAGUGGGACCCGAACUUGUUCCAAAAUCCAUUGGAACAUGGGGCCGGGGGUUCUCGGCGUCGUCUUUUGGGCUUCUCGACGUCGCUGCGUUUUUAUCCUGAGAUCCGUUUUCAUGGAGGAAAUGGAACACCUCCUUUGUUUGGUGCAUUUAGGCUGAUGAAUGUGAAAUUUUUUGCUCGCUUUCCACGCACUCCGUGGAGGUGUGUUUUCGGGGAAGGGUCGGAUUAUCUUUAUUGAUUGAGUGUCUCCUAAGGGAUAGCAUCUAAGGAGAUACCAAGAUAAAGGAACAUAUAGGUCACACAUCCCCGUUCUUAAACCUGGGAUUUAGAUACAGACUUCUAAAAACAUAAACGAAUGUAUUUUAUUCCUUAUUUUUAGGAUUUUUUUUAAAGAGUAGGCUUUCAGAACUCAGUUGGUGAAAAUACUGCAAUUUUAUCUUUGAAGUUUUUUGUUAAAAUGUUUCCCCACACCCCCCUAAAAAAUUAAGGAUUCUUUGUAGUUGUCUCCUGUUUUCUAUCUCCCAGGCCCUGAAAAGGAGCCUUUAAAAGUCAAUUCUACUCCAUUUGGCAAAGAGGGAACUGAAAUCUGGAAAGUAAGGACUUGCCCAAGGUCACUGACUUAGUGGCAGACUAGAGACUUGAACUCAGGUCUCCAUUCCCAGCAGAAAAAUAUGGCUCAGGAGACUAACCAGACCCCGGGGCCCAUGCUGUGUAGCACAGGAUGUGGCUUUUAUGGAAAUCCUAGGACAAAUGGAAUGUGUUCAGUUUGCUACAAAGAACAUCUUCAGAGGCAGCAAAAUAGUGGCAGAAUGAGCCCAAUGGGAACAGCUAGUGGUUCCAACAGUCCUACCUCAGAUUCUGCAUCUGUACAGAGAGCAGACACUAGCUUAAACAACUGUGAAGGUGCUGCUGGCAGCACAUCUGAAAAAUCAAGAAAUGUGCCUGUGGCUGCCUUGCCUGUAACUCAGCAAAUGACAGAAAUGAGCAUUUCAAGAGAGGACAAAAUAACUACCCCGAAAACAGAGGUGUCAGAGCCAGUUGUCACUCAGCCCAGUCCAUCAGUUUCUCAGCCCAGUACUUCUCAGAGUGAAGAAAAAGCUCCUGAAUUGCCCAAACCAAAGAAAAACAGAUGUUUCAUGUGCAGAAAGAAAGUUGGUCUUACAGGGUUUGACUGCCGAUGUGGAAAUUUGUUUUGUGGACUUCACCGUUACUCUGACAAGCACAACUGUCCGUAUGAUUACAAAGCAGAAGCUGCAGCAAAAAUCAGAAAAGAGAAUCCAGUUGUUGUGGCUGAAAAAAUUCAGAGAAUAUAAAUUACUUCUUGUGAAGAGACUGAAACUUUGUUUUUAUUUUAAUAUAUCGUAGGAAAACAUUAAAGAGCAGAUGCAUGGCCAUUUUUCUUUGAUGUUCUCCAGAGUUUUACAUUACACUUGUCUGUCUUAUAAUUGAUAUUUUAGGAUGUUUGGGUGUUUGUUACAGGCAGAAUUGGAUAGAUACAGCCCUACAAAUGUAUAUGCCCUCCCCUGAAAAAAAUUGGAUGAAAAUCUGCACAGCAAAGUGAAACACACAGAUAAUAGGAACAAAAUGUAGUUCCCAUGUGCCAAACAAAAUAAAUGAAAUCUCUGCAUGUUUGCAGCAUAUCUGCCUUUUGGGAAUGUAAUCAAGGUAUAAUCUUUGGCUAGUGUUAUGUGCCUGUAUUUUUUUAAAAUGGUACACCAGAAAAGGACUGGCAGUCUACUUCUACCAUAGUUAAACUUCACCCUCUUUAAUUUCACAACAUAUUCUUUGGAAGCAGGAAGAAAUGCUCAUAAAGAGGAUCAGACCUUCUUUCCCGUGAAACCAGUAUUUGGCGCCAUAUAUAAGCCUGGUUAAAUUGGUCAUCUAAAGCUGUCAAAUAAGACAUUCUGUGAAAGGUAAACAUCGAAACUGGUUAUAAGUAAAACCAUCAAGCCAACAACAGGGUCUUGAGAUAACCUUUGAAGCUUAUUGUACUGGCCUGCACCAGAAGAUGUCUGCAUUACUCAUUGCUAAAAAUGUGUAGCACAGAACUGCACUAGGAUUAAUUUGUUUACAAGAAGAAAUUUAAACUCUACGUUUGGUUUUCACAUACAGCAGCUCUAUUGAAUAACAUGCAUCUGAAUUUUAAGUUGCAAAGGUAUCUGAAUAAUUUUUCAUGUGCAUCUUUUGUCGAAUGUUUUGGUUCAAGAAAGAAUGUUUAAAGCUUUUUAAAAGACUUCAGUUCUUAAUGUAACUGUACCCUUCUGCAUGGAAAAUCAUAACCAACAUGGCUGCAGUAGACUUCUUAGUGGUAUCCAGCACCACUUGCAGAGGGCUGCUUUAUCAUAUUGUACUUGGGUGUAGGACUCUAGUGUUCUUGGGUGUAUUGCAUGGGCUGCAUUAUCUACAGCAUUGUACAAUAACAACUAGAAAAGGCAGUAUACUUCACUGAUGCUUGUCUGGUAAUAAUCACUUCUGUGUUAUAAUGGAAGGUUUUUUGUGAUGUAUGAAACUUGUGUUUUUUAUAUAUAAAUGAGUAUAGUUAGUGUUGUGGUAAUGCCUGUUUUCAUCUGUAAAUAGUUAAGUAUGUACACGAGGCACUACUUCUGAUUUAUUGCAAUGUUCAGUCCUAGUUUUUACUUUUAUUCUUAAAGCAUUCAGUUUUGCUUUCAAUUUUAUGUACCUUAGUUCUGAGUUAGACCUGCAGAUGUGUACAGAUAGUUCAUAUUUAUGUAUUGCACAUAAUCAUGCUAUUCAGCAUUGAUGCUAUAUUGUAUUAUGUAAAUAAUAAAAGCCAUGUACAGAGGGAAACUUCACUUGUUCAUUGGGUUUUUAAGCCAUAGUUGGAGUCCUAAAGGGGGAAAAUUAGAAAAUGUUACUUUACAUGGCUAUAUAAUUUUUUUUCCUUUGCCAUCGCUGAACUUGUUCAAGUGAUAAUCAAGAGAUAUUAGAAGCAUUUGCAGGUAUGAUACCUGAUAGGCAGUUUAUUUUUGAAGAAUUCAAUAGGCACCUUUGGGAUUAAAACAAUUUUAAAAUUUGAGAAAGAUGAAAUUUGAACAAUUAUGGCCUACCUCGCUUCUCCAUGUUGUAAAAGAUGAUGUUUUAUGACAAUUCUGAAGAAGAAAGUAGGUAUGACUUAGUUUACAAAAAGAGUUCUGUUUUAUUUCUGUUUUGGGUUUGGCUCUAAUACAGAGAUUCACCCAUGGACUUGGUCUCUGUAGCGUUUAUGCCAGAUCAUAAAGAACAAGGGGUGACAGGUACAUGUUGACUUUACCUGGGGUAAAUGAUUACCAGAGUGCAACUGUUGCUUCUCUGUGAUGGAGUUUGGGGUGGAAAUACCCUAGUUUUAUCUGUCAGUUCUUUGCAUGCUGCUACUUUUGCUUCAAGUUAGGGAGGUACAUAUGUAUGUCAAAGUUCCUAUACUGACAUAGGGUAGUAUUUCUCUGAAUAUGAAAAGUCACAAUUGAGUUGAAAAUUUAGAAGUUGAAGAUUUAGAAGGGCAACUUAAUUUUUCAAGUUAAAAAUGGAAGUAAGAGUGGUAUAGAGAAGGUAAGAUGAGCCCUCGGACUCCAUCACUCUGAAGGUCUGAGUAGUAGCAAGAGAUAGAUUUUUGUUUGGCCAGGCUGCAGUGCAAUGGCGUAAUCUUGGCUCACUGCAACCUCUGCCUCCUGGGUUCAAGUGAUUCUCCUGCCUCUGCCUCCUAAGUAGCUGGGAUCACAGGCACCAGCCACCACGCCCAGCUAAUUUUUGUAUUUUUAAUAGAGACAGUUUCUCCAUGUUGGUCAGGCUGGUCUUGAACUCCUGACCUCAGGUGAGCUGCCCGCCUCGGCCUCCCAAAGUGCUGGGAUUACAGGCGUGAGGCACCGCACCCGGCCAAUCAGUUUUUUUUGUUUUUUUUUUGUUUGUUUGUUUUACAAGAAACAUUAAACCAGAUCAGAACAAAGAUUUGUCAGGGUUGUCCAUUGACUGGGGAGAAAGGGAAUCAGUGUGUAAGGCACCUGAGAGGACUCAGUUCUACCCAAAUUCUUGCAUUCAAACCUGAAUGCAAGGCCAUGAAGUCCUUUGAAAUGUACAGAUAUUAAGCAAUUUAAUAAUAUACCAUGUUUCCCUUACAUAAGCAGACAAAUAUUUACACCCCCAUGACCUGAAGUUUUGUUAGGCUGUGACCACAUGAAUUCGCAGUAUAAAUGGGUGAGUCCUUUUUGAAAACCUCAUCUUCAGUGUGCCUGAUCUGUAAAACUAGAGCCUCAGGUUUGAUCCUAGGUAGGCUUCCCACAACGUGGGGAAAAUUAGUUUGUGAGGGAAAGCUGUUUCUGAGCAUUAUGGCAUAGUGAUUAAGAUGAGGGACCCUGGAACCAGCCCGUGAUUUUGGGCAAGUUAUUUUAGGUCCACUUUGGACUGCUUCAUCUCUUAAAUGAAGACAGCAACCACCUUCAGGAGUGUGAAGGUGACAACACUUAAAACUGUGCCUGGCACAUUGUAUUUGCUAUUGUCUUAAUGUUCUGGAAUAAUGGUUUCCAUAACUUGGGAAGAAAACUUUGAGAACAGGAUUGGUUACAUCAAGUUGUAUAGUGAAAAGAUAAAGAUUUGUUAUUUAAACUUGCAGUUUAAAGUCAUUAGAAUCAUUCUUUUCCGUAAGGCUUUCUUUGCAAGAGAUCUGCAUUAAAUAAAGUUGCUAGGAAAUAACUAAAAUUGGGGAAAUAAUCUAAUAAUAGCAAGAUGUUAAGCAUACUAUUAUUGUAUUUUGGGGGUUGGUAAUAACAUUCACAUGGAUUUAUCAAUACACACUGAGAAGCAAAGCCUCUCAAGCUGUCCCAUAUCCUCCAUUUCAAAGGCACACAUACAUUUUAGGUAACUCAUAAUUUAGAAAGGUUAUUUAAUCUUUUCCACAUGUAAAUAUUUGAAUAUGUACAAAGACUUGAUUUGACUCUUGUCUGUUUUUGUUUUGUUUUGUUUGUUUGAGACAGAGGCUCCGUCGCCCAGGCUGGAGUAAAAUGGCAUGGUCUCAGCUCACUGCAAGUUCCGCCUCCCGGGUUCACGCCAUUCUCCUGGCUCAGCCUCCGGAGUAGUUGGGACUACAGGCACCCGUCACCACACCUGGCUAAUGUUUUUUGUUUUUUGGGUUUUUUUGUAUUUUUAGUAGAGAGAGGGUUUCACCGUGUUAGCCAGGGUGGUCUCGAUCUCCUGACCUCAUGAUCCGCCCACCCCGGCCUCCCAAAAUGCUGGGAUUACAGGUGUGAGCCACUGCGCCUGGCCGACUCUUGUCUGUUUGAAUGCAAAGUUCUCAAUAGUGGUUUUUGUCCAUAAGUAUUAACUUAUAAUUUUGGAGAGUGAUAGGUAUGGUUGCUGGUUGAUUAGCAAUAAGAUUAUGUAGCCUUAAACUAGCUAGAAGAGUUUGCAUGGGUGAGGCAACAGGCUGUUAACAAAAAGAAACUGGAAAUACAGUUUCCCCUGUUUGUUUCUCCUGUUUGUACAAUCUGCUUUAAAAACAAGUGAACAUGCACCAUGUCAGUCAUGGUGAAUCGGCCAACAGCCAGCCCUUGCCAGUUGACAUCACAGUCUAAGAUGGGAAACUGGUACAGAUAGACAUGAAGAGAGCUUAGCAGUGGUUGAGGUGGUGACUAAAUAUACAGUCAUUGAAUAAAUACCGUGUAGCAAAUGUAAAAAAAAAAAAAAAAGUACAACAGAAUACAAAAGUGCCAUUUAAUAUUUUAUAGCUAUUUCUAUGCACAAGUGCUGGUUUUAAAUUUAUAUAAAAGCAAAGACUGUUUCUGUGUUUUCUUCCAGAGUAUUUCUGUUACAGCCAUAGAAGUAAAGUUAAUAAAUGUAAGACUUUUUUUGUUUUGUUUUGUGCCA